GCGGGUUUGAUGAACGCGGUUCCCGGGGAGACUGGUACGGUUGCUGUGUGCUAUGGAGCCGAGGGUCGUCAAGCCACCGGGGCAGGAUUUAGUAGUGGAGAGUCUCAAAAGCCGCUACGGACUCGGGGGCAGCUGCCCCGACGAGGUGAAGCCGCCGCCUGAGUAUGAUUUUUCAAAUUUUUAUCAGUCUAAGUAUAAGAGAAGAACUCUAACCUCCCCAGGUGAUUUGGAUAUCUACUCUGGAGAUAAAGUUGGUUCAUCGUUAAAAUAUUCUGAUGAAAGCAAGCAUUGUAGAACACCAUUGGGCAGCUUAUUCAAGCACGUAAAUGUGAAUUGCCUAGAUGAUGAACUGGAUUCUUUCCAUGAUUUGAAGAAACAGGAAACAGAAGAAGAGUUAAUUGAAAAUGAUUAUAGAGUUAGUACCUCGAAAAUAACCAAGCAGUCUUUUAAAGAAAUAGAAAAAGUUGCCUUGCCAACUAAUACGACCUCAUCGAGACCUCGGACUGAGUGUUGUAGUGAUGCAGGUGACUCUCCUUUGAAACCUGUCAGCUGUCCAAAAUCUAAAGCAUCAGACAAGCGGAGUUUACUUCCACAUCAGAUCAGUCAGAUAUAUGACGAAUUAUUUCAGAUACAUCUGAAAUUGCAGUGUGAAACUGCAGCACAACAGAAAUUUGCUGAAGAACUUCAAAAGCGAGAACGUUUUUUACUUGAAAGAGAACAACUGCUUUUCAGACAUGAAAAUGCCUUGAGUAAAAUUAAAGGUGUUGAAGAAGAGGUUCUUACAAGAUUUCAAAUUAUAAAAGAGCAGCAUGAUGCAGAAGUUGAACACUUAACCGAAGUUCUUAAGGAAAAGAAUAAAGAAACCAAGAGACUGAGGUCCUCUUUUGAUGCAUUGAAAGAAUUGAAUGAUACCUUAAAAAAACAGUUAAAUGAAGCAAGUGAAGAAAACAGGAAGAUAGACAUUCAGGCUAAAAGAGUUCAAGCUCGUUUAGAUAAUUUACAGAGGAAGUACGAGUUUAUGACAAUACAGAGAUUGAAAGGAAGUUCCCAUGCUGUUCAUGAAAUGAAAAGUUUAAAACAAGAAAAAGCACCAGUUUCAAAAACUUACAAGGUACCACUUAAUGGGCAAGUUUAUGAACUUUUAACUGUCUUCAUGGACUGGAUUUCGGAUCAUCAUCUUAGCAAAGUGAAACAUGAAGAAUCUGGAAUGGAUGGUAAAAAACCACAACUCAAAUUUGCUUCCCAGAGAAAUGAUAUUCAGGAGAAGUGUGUAAAGCUUUUGCCUCUAAUGACAGAGCAGCUACAGUGGAUGCCAUUUGUGAAUAUCAAACUUCACGAGCCUUUUGUAAAAUUUAUAUAUUGGUCCCUAAGGCAGCUAGAUGCUGGAGCACAGCACUCGACUAUGACAUCAACAUUGAGGAGAUUGGGUGAAGACAUUUUUAAAGGAGUGGUAACUAAAGGAAUUCAGGAUAAUUCUCCACAGCAUUCUGUGGAGAAUAAACCAAAGACAGCUGCUUUCUUUAAGAGCUCCAAUUUGCCAUUGAGAUUUUUAUCAACCUUAAUUGUUCUCAAAACAGUCACUCAAGUAGACACGGGGUUUCACCAUGUUCGCCAGGCUGGUCUCGAACUCCUGACCUCAUGAUCUGCCCGCCUCAACCUCCCAAAGUGCUGGGAUUACAGGCGUGAGCCACUGCGCCUGGCCAGUUGGUGAGUUUUGACACCACAGUGCUGUCUAGGGAAAACUCUUUAACUGUGUUUUUUCUCUACUCCCACAUGACAAUAAUCAUCCACACAGAAGAAGACUUCUGUGACAAAAUGUGUGGAGGUUUUUCCCCACAUACCAAGCAGCAGACACAAGCUGCUCCAAUUCACUUCUGACACGAUCCACCUGGAGAUAGUGUCAGAUCCCACAAGUUGGGCACUCAAGUCUCCAAGGCUGCCUCGUGCCACACCAGUUGCAAGUCCGGCCCUCUGGAACUUCUGACCAACUGGCUUCAAAUUGGGGUUCCUACAACCCCCUCUUUGGGUUUAAUUUGCUGGAGUAGCUCAUAGAACUCAGCGAAACACUUAACCAGUUUAUUAUAAAGGAUAUUGCAAAUGAUGUAGAUGAAGAGAGAGACAGAGCAAGGUAUAGGGGAAGGGGCAUGGAACUUCUGUCCCCUCCCUGGAGCACCACGCUCCAGAAAUCUCCAUAUGUCCAGCCGUCUGGAAGCUCUCUGAACCCAUUUCUCUGGGGUGUUUUGUUUUUUGUUGUUUGUUUGUUUGUUUUUGAGAUGGAGUUUUGCUCUUGUUGCCCAGGCUGGAGUGCAAUGGCGUGAUCUUGGCUUGCUGCAACCUCUGCCUCCCAGGUUCAAGCAAUUCUCCUGCCUCAGCCUCCCGAGUAGCUGGGCUUACAGGUGCCUGCCACCAUGCCCAGCUAAUUUUUGUACUUUUAGUAGAGAUGGGGUUUCACCACAUUGGCCAGGCUGGUGUUGAACUCCUGAAUUCAGGUGAUCCGCCCACCUCAGCCUCCCAAAAGUGCUGAUAUUACAGGCGUGAGCCACCGCGCCCGGCCUUUCUCUUGGGUUUUUAUGGAGGCUUCCUGACAUCACAAUUCUGUCCACCAGGAUAUAGGGCUGGACUCUCUCUGGGGAGGAUGUUAAGACCCACAAUCAGAAAGUCCAGGAAAGAUUAGAGUCCUGGCUUGGGCCAAGUGAAAGGAGGGCAGGAGAAGGUCAGAGACCUUCCCCUGAGGCCUAACACACCCAACAUCAUAACAAAGACUAAUGAGACGAAAACCUAUAUAUAUAUAUCAUAACACCACAGAUACUAAGCUCUUUAUACCUUAUCUCUGAAUACUAUUAUCCUCAUAUUAGUGAUGAGGUUUACAAAGGUAGAUAAUUGUGCCAAAACGAUACAAUCUGCAUUUGACAGAGCCUAAUUUAGCCUCUAUCAAUUGCUGAAGCCUACCUUCUUAAGCCUAUUUUAUGACUACCUAAGAGCAUGUACUUCCUGAGAUAACCAAAGAAAUAAACACCUACAUAGCACUUACUAUGUUAUAGGCCGAGCACUUUAUAUAUAUUAACUCAUUUAAUCCUCACAACAGUUCAUGAGAUGUCAAUAUUAUUAUUGUAAUUUUACAAAUGAGGAAAUUGAGGCAUAAAAAAGUUUAGCUGCACACAAUCAGUAUGUGAUGCUCAAUCUCUGAAAUAAAAUUUAACUGUAAGAUACAACUCUUCUUUAUGGAAAGAAAGGAACACUUGUACACUGUUUGUGGGAGUGUAAAUUAGUUCAGCCAUUGUGGAAGACAGUGUGGCAUUUCCUCAAAGACCUAAAGACAAAUGCCAUUCAACCCAACAAUCCCAUUACUGGGUAUAUACCCAAACUAAUAGAAAUUGUUCUAUUAUAAGGACACAUGCAUGUGUUGUGUUCAUUGCAGCACUGUUCACAAUAGCAAAGUCACGGAAUCAACCCAAAUGCCCAUCGAAGAUAACCUGGAUAAAGAAAAUGUGGUACAUAUACACUAUGGAAUACUAUGCAGCCAUUAAAAAGAAUGAGAUUAUGUCCUUUGCAGGGACAUGGAUGGACUUGGAGGCCGUUAUCCUUAACAGACUAAUGCAGGAACAGAAAAUCAAAUAACACAUGUUCUCAUUUAUAAGUGGGAGCUAAAUGAUGAGAACACAUGGAUACAUAAGGGGAACAACACACACUGGGGCCUAUCAGAGGGUGGGAGGAGGGACAGGAUCAGGAAAAAUAACUAAUGGGUACUAGUCUUAAUACCUGGGUGAUGAAAUAAUCUGUACAACAAACUCCUAUGACACAAGUGUACCUGUGUAACAAACCUGCACAGGUACCCCUGAACUAAAAUAAAAUAAAAAAACCCAACCAUUACAGAAGUAAAAUGAGCAAAUAUAAUGUGUCACUGAGAGGAUAUAGGCACAAUUUUGUUUGUAUCAAAGUUAAUAUUUUUGAAAUGCAUUCUGCUCACAAACAUCACCAAAAUACAUCAUAACCUUUCGUGAGAUCUACCUUAAGAAAUAAUUGCAAAAGUAAAAAUGUUCCAAGGUGUUAAUAUGCUGUUUGUAAUAAUGAGAAAAGAUAAAUAGCUGAUAGACCCACAAUCGGAAUAGUGAAGAAAAUGAACAUCAACCGAGUUCUUGGACUUUGCUGGCAUUGUUUUAGUCAUUGUACUUGAUUGUUUCAGAUUUAUUCCCUGCAAUAACUAUGAGGUAGGUCAUGGUGUCAUUUUUACAGAAGAGCAAACUGAGGGUCAGUCUAAUAUAAUUGACCCAGAUUUUUCUAGAAAUAUUGGGCCCUUAACCAUAUCAUGAGCAUAGUACAAUAUUAUAUGUCAUUAACAAUAAGUAUGGAGAUACAGAAAUCUAUGUGUAUUUUAAUUAAUAAAACCUUCAAUAUAUGUGUACCAAUUUAAUCUAGAAAUUGUUAAAAGAAGUUGUAGGAACUUUAUCUGAUAGAAUUAUUUGGUUUACUGAUAGCUUUCUUUUUUUUUUUUUUGAGAGAUGGGAUCUCACGCUAUCACUCAGGCUGGAAUGCAGUGGUGCAAGCAUAACUUACCACAACCUUGAACUCCUGGGCUCAAGCAGUCCUCUUGCCUCAGGCUUCCAAGUAGCUGGGACUACAGGCAUGCACUACGAUGACCAUCUAAUUUUUUAUUUUUUGUAGAGAUGAGCUCUUGCCAUGUUGCCCAAGCUGGUCUCAAACUCCUGGGCUGAAGCUGUCUUCCCCUCUUGGCCCCUCAAAGCAGUGGAGUUACAGGCACCAGCCAUCCCCAGCCAACUGUCUUCUA